GUCAGGGAAGCGGCGCGCGCGCGCGGGCGGCGGGCGGGCUGGGGAUCCGCCGCGCAGUGCCAGCGCCAGCGCCAGACCCGCGCCCCGCGCUCUCCGGCCCGUCGCCUGCCUUGGGACUCGCGAGCCCGCACUCCCGCCCUGCCUGUUCGCUGCCCGAGUAUGGAGCUGCUGUGUUGCGAAGGCACCCGGCACGCGCCCCGGGCCGGGCCGGACCCGCGGCUGCUGGGGGACCAGCGUGUCCUGCAGAGCCUGCUCCGCCUGGAGGAGCGCUACGUACCCCGCGCCUCCUACUUCCAGUGCGUGCAGCGGGAGAUCAAGCCGCACAUGCGGAAGAUGCUGGCUUACUGGAUGCUGGAGGUACCGCCCGGACGCGUCCCCCUCCCCCACCGCUCCCGGGUCUGGACACACCGGGGCCGCCCUGUCGGGACAUCCCGGUCCCCACAGCAAUCUGCAGGAUGCUCCGAGGCUAAGACUCCCGGGGCCUGGCCUUUCACUAGGGCACCCACGCCAGCUGCCUCCCUUGCUUUCCCGAGCCCUAAUCGGCUCCUCCCGACAGUGACUGCCAGUCACUUGGCACCCUAACUGUGCCUCUCUUCGGGCCGAGCAAACGGGACCAAGGACACUCUCUCCCCUUCGGCUUCUCACAGCGUCUCCCGCUUCCCUCCGCCUCCCGGCCUUCUCCGGAGAGCGCGCCUGGAAAACCCUGGGCUCGGCCGCCCCCGCCCGGGAGCCGGUUCCUGUGUCUUUCGCGGGGUUCUGGCGGGGAAGGCGAUGGGGGUGGCGCGCGCCCUGUUCCGGCCGACAGGGAAAUGAAAAGUGCAGGAGGCAGCGGCAGGAGCCUCCUCCCUUCCCCUCGGGUAUGUGAGGAGCAGCGCUGUGAGGAGGAAGUCUUCCCCCUGGCCAUGAACUACCUGGAUCGCUACCUGUCUUGCGUCCCCACCCGAAAGGCGCAGUUGCAGCUCCUGGGUGCGGUCUGCAUGCUGCUGGCCUCCAAGCUGCGCGAGACCACGCCCCUGACCAUCGAAAAACUGUGCAUCUACACCGACCACGCUGUCUCUCCCCGCCAGUUGCGGGACUGGGAGGUGCUGGUCCUAGGGAAGCUCAAGUGGGACCUGGCUGCUGUGAUUGCACAUGAUUUCCUGGCCUUCAUUCUGCACCGGCUCUCUCUGCCCCGUGACCGACAGGCCUUGGUCAAAAAGCAUGCCCAGACCUUUUUGGCCCUCUGUGCUACAGAUUAUACCUUUGCCAUGUACCCGCCAUCCAUGAUCGCCACGGGCAGCAUUGGGGCUGCAGUGCAAGGCCUGGGUGCCUGCUCCAUGUCCGGGGAUGAGCUCACAGAGCUGCUGGCAGGGAUCACUGGCACUGAAGUGGACUGCCUGCGGGCCUGUCAGGAGCAGAUCGAAGCUGCACUCAGGGAGAGCCUCAGGGAAGCCUCUCAGACCAGCUCCAGCCCAGCGCCCAAAGCCCCCCGGGGCUCCAGCAGCCAAGGGCCCAGCCAGACCAGCACUCCUACAGAUGUCACAGCCAUACACCUGUAGCCCUGGAGAGGCCCUCUGGAGUGGCCACUAAGCAGAGGAGGGGCCGCUGCCACCCACCUCCCUGCCUCCAGGAACCACACCACAUCUAAGCCUGAAGGGGCGUCUGUUCCCCCUUCACAAAGCCCAAGGGAUCUGGUCCUACCCAUCCCCGCAGUGUGCACUAAGGGGCCCGGCCAGCCAUGUCUGCAUUUCGGUGGCUAGUCAAGCUCCUCCUCCCUGCAUCUGACCAGCAGCGCCUUUCCCAACUCUAGCUGGGGGUGGGCCAGGCUGAUGGGACAGAAUUGGAUACAUACACCAGCAUUCCUUUUGAACGCCCCCCCCCACCCCUGGGGGCUCUCAUGUUUUCAACUGCCAAAAUGCUCUAGUGCCUUCUAAAGGUGUUGUCCCUUCUAGGGUUAUUGCAUUUGGAUUGGGGUCCCUCUAAAAUUUAAUGCAUGAUAGACACAUAUGAGGGGGAAUAGUCUAGAUGGCUCCUCUCAGUACUUUGGAGGCCCCUAUGUAGUCCGUGCUGACAGCUGCUCCUAGAGGGAGGGGCCUAGGCCUCAGCCAGAGAAGCUAUAAAUUCCUCUUUGCUUUGCUUUCUGCUCAGCUUCUCCUGUGUGAUUGACAGCUUUGCUGCUGAAGGCUCAUUUUAAUUUAUUAAUUGCUUUGAGCACAACUUUAAGAGGACAUAAUGGGGUCCUGGCCAUCCCACAAGUGGUGGUAACCCUGGUGGUUGCUGUUUUCCUCCCUUCUGCUACUGGCAAAAGGAUCUUUGUGGCCAAGGAGCUGCUAUAGCCUGGGGUGGGGUCAUGCCCUCCUCUCCCAUUGUCCCUCUGCCCCAUCCUCCAGCAGGGAAAAUGCAGCAGGGAUGCCCUGGAGGUGGCUGAGCCCCUGUCUAGAGAGGGAGGCAAGCCCUGUUGACACAGGUCUUUCCUAAGGCUGCAAGGUUUAGGCUGGUGGCCCAGGACCAUCAUCCUACUGUAAUAAAGAUGAUUGUGAAAUAAAA